GUUGGCGGCGUGGAGGGGCGCCGGUGGCCACGUUGGUGUCAACCUCCUUCGUGAAGCUCACACCUCCCCCGCCCCGGGAGGGGUUUGCCCGCCACUGUCGCUGAAUGAUUGCAUCAUCGAAAGCAGAAAACCACUUUUGCAUCCUUCGGCCUCUGGCGUGCCUGCCAUGACGUCAUAGCUCUGCGGAGGUGGAAGUUGGGGAGCUUUGAGGCCUCCUCUGUAGAAUGGAAACUCUGUACCCCUGCUUGUCUUAGGACCUCAUGGAUCCCAGGGGGACCAAGAGAGGAGCUGAGAAGACAGAGGUAGCUGAGCCUCGGAACAAACUACCUCGUCCAGCACCUUCUCUGCCCACAGACCCUGCCCUCUACUCUGGGCCCUUUCCUUUCUACCGGCGCCCUUCGGAACUGGGCUGCUUCUCCCUGGAUGCUCAACGCCAGUACCAUGGAGAUGCCCGAGCCCUGCGCUACUAUAGCCCACCCCCCACUAACGGUCCAGGCCCCAACUUUGACCUCAGAGACGGAUACCCGGAUCGAUACCAGCCCCGGGACGAGGAGGUCCAGGAAAGGCUGGACCACCUGCUGUGCUGGCUCCUGGAACACCGAGGCCGGUUGGAGGGGUGAGCAAAGCGUGGGGUCCAGGCUGGCUGGCAGAGGCCAUAGUGACGUGGCGGGGGCACCUGACAAAACUGCUGACGACACCGUAUGAGCGGCAGGAGGGCUGGCAGCUGGCAGCCUCCCGGUUCCAGGGAACACUAUACCUGAGUGAAGUGGAGACACCGAACGCUCGGGCCCAGAGGCUUGCUCGGCCACCGCUCCUCCGGGAGCUUAUGUACAUGGGAUACAAAUUUGAGCAGUACAUGUGUGCAGACAAACCUGGAAGCUCCCCAGACCCCUCUGGGGAGGUUAACACCAACGUGGCCUUCUGCUCUGUGCUACGCAGCCGCCUGGGAAGCCACCCUCUGCUCUUCUCAGGGGAGGUAGACUGCACAGACCCCCAAGCCCCAUCCACACAGCCCCCAACCUGCUAUGUGGAGCUCAAGACCUCCAAGGAGAUGCACAGCCCUGGCCAAUGGAGGAGUUUCUACAGACACAAGCUCCUGAAAUGGUGGGCUCAGUCAUUCCUCCCAGGGGUCCCGAAUGUUGUUGCUGGCUUCCGUAACCCAGACGGUUUUGUCUCUUCCCUCAAGACCUUUCCUACCAUGAAGAUGUUUGAAUAUGUCAGGAAUGACCGUGACGGCUGGAAUCCCUCUGUGUGCAUGAACUUCUGUGCCGCCUUCCUUAGCUUUGCCCAGAGCACGGUUGUCCAGGAUGACCCCAGGCUCGUUCAUCUCUUCUCUUGGGAGCCUGGCGGCCCAGUCACCGUGUCUGUACACCAAGAUGCACCUUACGCCUUCCUGCCCAUAUGGUAUGUGGAAGCUAUGACUCAGGACCUCCCAUCACCCCCCAAGACUCCCUCUCCCAAAUAGUAAUGCUUUAGAGGGAGGCAGUCAUAUCUCUGUGUGCAGAUAAUAAAAGCAUAUUUCUAAGA